AGUCCCUGUCCUGCGCCCGCGCGCCCCGGGAGCCUACCCAGCACGCGCUCCGCGCCCACUGGUUCCCUCCAGCCGCCGCCGUCCAGCCGAGUCCCCACUCCGGAGUCGCCGCUGCCGCGGGGACAUGGUCCUCUGCGUUCAGGGGUGAGCACCCCCUUGUAAGCUCAGGGCUACUGUUGGGUGUCAGGGAACAAAGUUUUAGACUGCUGCGCUCCAAAGCGGGCACACACAUGUACCUAGAACACACCAGCCACUGUCCCCACCAUGAUGAUGACACAGCCAUGGACACACCCCUGCCCAGACCUCGUCCUUUGCUGGCUGUGGAGCGGACUGGGCAGCGGCCCCUGUGGGCCCCGUCCCUGGAACUGCCCAAGCCAGUCAUGCAGCCCUUGCCUGCUGGGGCCUUCCUCGAGGAGGUGGCAGAGGGUACCCCAGCCCAGACAGAGAGUGAGCCAAAGGUGCUGGACCCAGAGGAGGAUCUGCUGUGCAUAGCCAAGACCUUCUCCUACCUUCGGGAAUCUGGCUGGUAUUGGGGUUCCAUUACGGCCAGCGAGGCCCGACAACACCUGCAGAAGAUGCCAGAAGGCACGUUCUUAGUACGUGACAGCACGCACCCCAGCUACCUGUUCACGCUGUCAGUGAAAACCACUCGUGGCCCCACCAAUGUACGCAUUGAGUAUGCCGACUCCAGCUUCCGUCUGGACUCCAACUGCUUGUCCAGGCCACGCAUCCUGGCCUUUCCGGAUGUGGUCAGCCUUGUGCAGCACUAUGUGGCCUCCUGCACUGCUGAUACCCGAAGCGACAGCCCCGAUCCUGCUCCCACCCCGGCCCUGCCUAUGCCUAAGGAGGAUGCGCCUAGUGACCCAGCACUGCCUGCUCCUCCACCAGCCACUGCUGUACACCUAAAACUGGUGCAGCCCUUUGUACGCAGAAGCAGUGCCCGCAGCCUGCAACACCUGUGCCGCCUUGUCAUCAACCGUCUGGUGGCCGACGUGGACUGCCUGCCACUGCCCCGGCGCAUGGCCGACUACCUCCGACAGUACCCCUUCCAGCUCUGACUGUACGGGGCAAUCUGCCCACCCUCACCCAGUCGCACCCUGGAGGGGACAUCAGCCCCAGCUGGACUUGGGCCCCCACUGUCCCUCCUCCAGGCAUCCUGGUGCCUGCAUACCUCUGGCAGCUGGCCCAGGAAGAGCCAGCAAGAGCAAGGCAUGGGAGAGGGGAGGUGUCACACAACUUGGAGGUAAAUGCCCCCAGGCCGCAUGUGGCUUCAUUAUACUGAGCCAUGUGUCAGAGGAUGGGGAGACAGGCAGGACCUUGUCUCACCUGUGGGCUGGGCCCAGACCUCCACUCGCUUGCCUGCCCUGGCCACCUGAACUGUAUGGGCACUCUCAGCCCUGGUUUUUCAAUCCCCAGGGUCGGGUAGGACCCCUACUGGCAGCCAGCCUCUGUUUCUGGGAGGAUGACAUGCAGAGGAACUGAGAUCGACAGUGACUAGUGACCCCUUGUUGAGGGGUAAGCCAGGCUAGGGGACUGCACAAUUAUACACUAUUUAUUUAUUUAUUCUCCUUGGGGUUGGUGUCAGGGGCGAGCCAACCCCACCUCUAUGCCCUGAGCCCUGGUAGUCCAGAGACCCCAACUCUGCCCUGGCUUCUCUGGUUCUUCCCUGUGGAAAGCCCAUCCUGAGACAUCUUGCUGGAACCAAGGCAAUCCUGGAUGUCCUGGUACUGACCCACCCGUCUGUGAAUGUGUCCACUCUCUUCUGCCCCCAGCCAUAUUUGGGGAGGAUGGACAACUACAAUAGGUAAGAAAAUGCAGCCGGAGCCUCAGUCCCCAGCAGAGCCUGUGUCUCACCCCCUCACAGGACAGAGCUGUAUCUGCAUAGAGCUGGUCUCACUGUGGCGCAGGCCCCGGGGGGAGUGCCUGUGCUGUCAGGAAGAGGGGGUGCUGGUUUGAGGGCCGCCACUGCAGUUCUGCUAGGUCUGCUUCCUGCCCAGGAAGGUGCCUGCACAUGAGAGGAGAGAAAUACACGUCUGAUAAGACUUCAUGAAAUAAUAAUUAUAGCAAAGAACAGUUUGGUGGUCUUUUCUCUUCCACUGAUUUUUCUGUAAUGACAUUAUACCUUUAUUACCUCUUUAUUUUAUUACCUCUAUAAUAAAAUGAUACCUUUCAUGUA